GUCGGUGCUGGAGAUCGCGGCUCGGUGCAGGCGGCGCCCAUGCCUCCUCUCCUCCACUAGCCCGCGCGCCAGUCCGCCUGCCGGGGCCGGCUCUCCGCCUCCUGCCUCCCGUCGCAGCCGCGCAGCCGCCGCAGAGUCCGCGGCGCCACCGCUCGCCCUCCAGGAAUGCAUGGCCUGAGUCUCGUCAUGAGGAGACAUCAGAUGGAUUCAAAUUGAGGGUGACCUGAGUCAUCUGAGAGAAUAAAAGGUUUGGCUCACUAAAACUGUCAAGGAUGAGAGGCAAGGAAAGACCGAGAAACUACUCCACACUGAAGAAGAGAUUGGAUAACUAAAUGUUCUGCCACUUGCUGGGAAAACAGCAACAGAAGGAUAUUAAGGAGCCACCCCUAUAAUUUACCCAGAUAGCCCCAGCAAGGUCAAAGACAUAUCAUGUCCCAAGGAGAAAAGCUGCAGGCAUCUGAGGAUAAAUCACUGUGAAACAGCUUUGACCAUAAAGCUGACUUGGAAGACUUUGACUCCAAGGUGCAAGGUGGUUUGGACACCCUCAAUAUUGCCUGCUCUUUUCUAGUCAAACCUGAUUCAUGAAAUGGAAUGAAGCUGAAAAAUCAUCUACUUCUUUGUUUGUGGAUUUGAGAGAAGAUUGGGAUGGUCUUAAGUGCAUAAAACGAGACUCUAACUGCAGCGAUGAGUUCAGAUGAGAAGGGCAUUUCCCCUGCUCAUAAAACAUCCACUCCAACCCAUAGAAGUGCCUCCUCUUCAACAUCCUCCCAAAGGGACAGUAGGCAGCAACCUGAAAGGAUGGGGAUCGGGGAGAGUCGUUAAAGAGAAGCUCAGAUCAGAGAUACCUGACUGGAAGAUUAAAAGUAUUCACAUACUGGAGAGGACUGCUUCCUCUAGCACCGAGCCCUCUGUAAGUCGGCAAUUGCUAGAACCGGAGCCAGUCCCCCUCUCCAAGGAAGCUGACAGCUGGGAAAUUAUAGAAGGGCUGAAAAUAGGCCAAACCAAUGUCCAGAAACCAGACAAACAUGAGGGCUUUAUGCUGAAGAAAAGAAAAUGGCCUUUAAAAGGCUGGCACAAGCGUUUUUUUGUCCUGGAUAAUGGAAUGUUAAAGUAUUCAAAGGCACCACUCGAUAUUCAGAAAGGAAAGGUCCAUGGGAGCAUAGAUGUGGGACUCUCAGUCAUGUCAAUUAAAAAGAAAGCUCGAAGAAUAGACCUUGACACCGAAGAGCACAUCUAUCAUUUGAAGGUGAAAUCCCAGGACUGGUUUGAUGCAUGGGUCUCCAAACUGCGACAUCAUCGGUUGUAUCGUCAGAAUGAAAUUGUGAGAUCACCAAGAGAUGCUAGUUUUCACAUAUUUCCUUCAACGUCCACAGCUGAAUCCUCACCAGCUGCUAAUGUUUCUGUAAUGGAUGGAAAGAUGCAACCAAACAGCUUUCCGUGGCAGUCCCCUUUACCAUGCAGCAAUAGCCUCCCUGCAACGUGCACAACUGGCCAGAGUAAAGUGGCAGCCUGGUUACAGGACUCGGAAGAGAUGGACAGGUGUGCAGAAGAUCUUGCACAUUGCCAGUCAAACCUUGUGGAACUUAGCAAACUCCUGCAAAAUUUGGAAAUACUUCAGAGAACUCAGUCGGCACCUAACUUUACUGACAUGCAGGCUAACUGUGUAGAUAUUUCAAAGAAAGACAAGCGGGUCACAAGACGAUGGAGAACAAAAAGUGUCAGCAAAGAUACAAAAAUACAACUGCAGGAAGGGCCACCCGCGAAGGGCCAGUUCAGCACAACUCGGCGCCGGCAGAGGCUAGCGGCAGCAGUGGCUACAACAGUUCCUUUCAGUGCUACCAUGUCACCAGUUCGCUUGCAUUCCUCCAACCCCAACCUUUGUGCAGAUAUUGAAUUUCAGACUCCCCCUAGCCACCUCACUGACCCUCUGGAAAGUUCAACAGAUUAUACAAAGCUGCAAGAAGAAUUUUGUCUAAUCGCACAGAAAGUGCAUUCUCUUUUGAAGUCUGCAUUUAAUAGCAUAGCUAUAGAGAAGGAGAAGCUGAAGCAGAUGGUUUCCGAGCAGGAUCACAGUAAAGGCCACAGCACGCAGAUGGCACGGCUCCGACAGUCACUGUCUCAGGCACUCAACCAGAAUGCUGAACUAAGGAGUCGGUUGAACAGAAUACAUUCAGAGUCUAUUAUUUGUGAUCAGGUUGUCAGUGUAAAUAUUAUUCCUAGCCCUGAUGAGGCUGGUGAGCAAAUCCAUGUCAGUCUCCCCUUAUCACAGCAAGUAGCCAAUGAGAGCCGCCUCUCCAUGUCAGAGUCUGUUUCUGAGUUCUUUGAUGCCCAAGAGGUGCUCCUCUCUGCAAGUUCGUCAGAGAAUGAGGCUUCAGAUGAUGAGUCUUACAUCAGUGAUGUGAGUGAUAAUAUAUCUGAAGACAACACCAGUGUUGCAGACAAUAUUUCUCGGCAAAUCCUGAAUGGGGAGCUUACAGGAGGGGCCUUCCGAAAUGGGCGUCGAGCAUGCCUGCCAGCUCCUUGUCCUGACACCAGUAACAUUAACCUGUGGAAUAUCUUGAGGAACAACAUUGGUAAAGACCUGUCUAAAGUCUCUAUGCCUGUGGAGCUAAACGAGCCGCUCAACACCCUGCAGCACCUCUGUGAGGAAAUGGAAUACAGCGAGCUCCUGGACAAGGCUUCGGAAACUGAUGAUCCAUAUGAGCGCAUGGUUCUCGUUGCCGCAUUUGCAGUUUCAGGAUACUGCUCCACCUAUUUCAGAGCAGGAAGUAAGCCAUUCAACCCAGUCCUUGGGGAGACUUAUGAAUGCAUUAGAGAAGACAAGGGAUUCCGCUUUUUCUCAGAACAGGUUAGCCAUCAUCCACCCAUUUCUGCCUGUCACUGUGAAUCAAAGAAUUUUGUGUUUUGGCAAGAUAUCAGAUGGAAAAACAAGUUCUGGGGGAAGUCGAUGGAAAUCCUGCCUGUUGGAACACUGAAUGUCAUGCUUCCAAAGUAUGGAGAUUACUAUGUGUGGAAUAAAGUCACCACUUGCAUACACAACAUCCUCAGUGGGAGAAGAUGGAUAGAACAUUAUGGAGAAGUAACCAUCAGAAAUACCAAAAGCAGUGUUUGCAUUUGCAAACUCACAUUUGUCAAGGUGAAUUAUUGGAAUUCUAACAUGAAUGAAGUCCAGGGGGUGGUGAUAGAUCAGGAGGGGAAGGCGGUGUACCGGCUGUUUGGAAAGUGGCAUGAAGGACUCUACUGUGGUGUGGCCCCCUCUGCAAAGUGCAUUUGGAGACCAGGUUCCAUGCCAACAAACUAUGAGCUGUACUAUGGCUUCACAAGGUUUGCUAUUGAGCUCAAUGAGUUAGAUCCAGUACUAAAAGAUCUCCUUCCACCAACAGACGCCCGGUUCCGGCCAGAUCAAAGAUUUUUGGAAGAAGGAAAUUUAGAAGCUGCAGCAUCAGAGAAGCAAAGAGUAGAGGAACUCCAGAGAUCUCGGAGACGAUAUAUGGAAGAAAACAAUCUUGAACAUAUACCAAAAUUUUUUAAAAAAGUUAUUGAUGCCAAUCAAAGAGAAGCCUGGGUUUCUAACGACACCUACUGGGAGCUUCGAAAGGACCCUGGGUUUAGCAAAGUAGACAGCCCUGUUCUUUGGUAGACUGGGAAUGUAGAGCUAGCCAACAUAUCACAUUCUGAAUGAAUAAAUAACUAUGCACAAUUAUGUUUCUUAUAGCUAUGUGUGGUUUCUGGGUCAACUGAAAACCUACCAUUUGCUUUUCUAUUCAUCUUUAUAAUGGACUUUCAGAAGUGCAUUAGACAAGGCCCCUAACCACUUUGGGAUCCUUUCUGUUUUGCUGCAACCAUAUUCCUUAAAAAAAAAAAAAAAAAAAAAAAAAAAAUCCACACCGUCCUUGGAAAGCAGAAUAAAAGGAGCAGAAUAUAAAAUCCAAAGUCUGACCAGUUUGUAAAGAAAAACAAAUGGUAACUGGUGCUUAAAGCUGAUCAAGAAAGUUAACAACAACAUAGAAACCACACGAUUGUUCCACUGUCUGGAAGCACCAUCCCCUAUCGCAGGACUCCUGGGCCACAAGCAGUCGGUCAGUGCAGACUUCAAGUGUGUCUGUUUGAUGUGGUGUGAUUGUGCUGGCCUUGUCGAAAAAGAUGUGAUGCUUCUCAGAACCUGUUCCAUCUGUAUGCCAUUGUUCAUGCCUUAAGAAAUGCAAAGAUGUACAAUAAAUCAUUUUUAAAAUGUGUGCUCAUAGGUUUAUGUGAAGAACAGAUUUUUUGAAUCAUGGCAUGAUUCACUUUCUCAAUCAGGACAAUUAUGAGACUAACUUAAAUGGGUUUUUUAAAAGUGAACAACACGUGCUUUACUCUGAUAAGUCAGUUACCAUAUGGUAUGUCUGAAGGGAAAGAAGGAAAAGACGUGCUAAGUAGAUCUCUGUAUUUACGUGGCUCGUUAAUUUCCUGUCCUGCGUCCAGAUAAUAAACCAUCCCUCUUCCACCUAACCUCACAGUGUGCCCUAUUAUUUGGAAAAAUCUGUCUUUGAUUUGGACAUUUGGUCAUCAGUGUUAAAACCUUAAAAGGAAAUAACAAAAAGCAUAUGGAAUUCCUGUGUGGGCUUAGUAGUACUAUAAAUGUAAUUGUUUUUGAGUGAAGCACCAUGUAAUCCAUGUCUCAAUCCCAUGCCCGCUCCACUGACACUAGUCGAAUUCCACUGAGAACAGAAGCAAGAAUAAUAGUAGUUUAUUUGCAUUGUUUAAAUGAAUUCUAUGCAAAAUCAUAUUUCAAAUUUUCAUCAAGUGAUUCCAUAUGGUACAUGGCUACAUAUUAAGCAUUUACCUUGCUAUUGGCAGAGAUAUGAAACUUAAGCUAAGGAAUGUAUCCAUCCCAAAGCAGGAAAGCAGAAGUGUGUUUUGCAUACUUCAGGAUUUGUUUUUCCUCCACUAAUAUACAGAGGCUUUUGCAGAAAACUUGCAUCAGUAUUCCUGUUUCUGCACGUAGGUGACUAUAUAAAUGCCUGUAUGUUUUUUUUAAAAUAUCUCCUCAGAGAUUUUCCUAGGGAAUUAUAAAAUUACAUAUAUUUUAUUGUUAGUUAGAUGUUUAUUCUUGGAUUCUUACCAUUAGAAUUUAAGUGUUAUUUAAAACUCUGAUACAGUUACAGACACUUUACAUUUUAUUAUGAGGUGUUGAUUUUAGUGGUAUUUCUCCUCAGCAAAGCAUUCCUAAUAAUGGCUAAUACACCAUCAAAUGAAAAACUGCUGAUGAGAGUGUAAGAGAAAGCGCUAACGUUUCCACUAGAUGGCGCAAUAUUUUAUUUAUCCAAAACUCCUCCCUUGCAUCUGAGUUUUUAUGUUAUGUGUACAGUCUGCAUUAGCUUAGAAUGGAAUUUCAUUCUCAGGUAAAUUUUCGAAUCCAUCACCAGAUCUAAGCAUUCUGCUUCAACAAUACCCUCUCUAUUCCUCUCAUUCCCAUUUUAAAUCCAUAGGUGGCUUGCCCUGCGGCAGUAAAAUCUUCCCCUUGAUAUUGAUUCUUUUUCUGCUCAUUCAUCUUGAUGUUCUUUUUCUGCAUCCUGAGAUACAUGUCGUUAAUUUUAAUAAGAAUCCUAUUGACUUCCUCACGGGAGUCUGUUCUCCUAUGGUUGAUAAAGCUUUAAAUACUAUUUAAAGUGGUUCUGGUCUGUACUUACUAGCACUUCCCUGAACAGUCUCAAAAUAGCCUAAACAUAAGAAAACAAUCCUGCAAAGUAAAGGUUUUUACAAGCAGAGAUGAAGGAAAGGGAGCAGCAGCUGACCAUCAGAUGUGGUAUCAGGUAGCUGGAAGAGGAUCCAGGACCCAUCAGGGAAGCAACGACUGUACUUAGCAAUUUGGGUUAUAAUUACAAAAAAGAAAAAAUAGUAGAAAGGAUCUUUACCAGACAGUAAGGUCAUGGUACAAAUCAGGUGAGUGAAUGUUGGUCAGAGGUAGCCUGACACUCUGAUGAGGACUUCAAGAUGAGAAUGAGAAAAAUGUCUAUUAAAAUCACUACAUUUGAUAAUAUCUCAGAUUUAGAAUCUCUUUUGGGAUUCAGAUAGUCUGAUUAUUCCAAUUCAAGUGUUCAGUUAAGUUUUAGUUACUAUUCCUAUAAUACCCAAUUCACUAAUAUCAUAUCUCCUGUGGAAUAUUCAUUGGUGCGAUGGCCUCAUCCCCUUUUUUACUUUUUAUUGACAUGGUGGUUAUAAAAUGAAGAGACUUACUCUAUUGGAAUUUUCAUCUACGUAGUAUUUGGGCUGUCAAGACUAAAUAGCAAAAGGGUAGAAUAUUAGAUCAUUCUCUUAAUAAGACCUGAUUUAUUCCUUAGGAUGUUAUACAAACCUUUUUAUUUCAGGCCUACUUUCUUGUUUUUUCCUAAAAGGAUCUAGGAUAGAGGAGAACAUAAUAUGCCUGUAUACUUCUCCCAUGGUUUAUUCAUAAGCUGCUUCAUCUCAUUGGAGAUGGUCAUUGAGGAGAGCAGUAAUAAGUGACGAUGAUUCUGAGGACUUGGCUAGACUGAGCGGAUCAAUGGCACACACCAGCACUGGUAGAGGCUGACCAGAAGCUCAUCGAUUCCAUAUGCUGUCACCCAGGGUGCAGAUUUACUCUCUUUUGCUGUUAUUUUAUUGUUUUUCUUAAAUUAAGCCAUUGUUUUUCAUGGAUUAUUUUUAAAAUACCUACCCCAUAAUUUUCAGGCAAUUGUAAAAAUAAACCUUAUUUAAGAUAACUUUUAAUGGUACAUAUCAACUAUAUGUGGGGAAAAAAUGCAAUUUUCUGGGCAAGAGAAACCAAAGGAUUUUCAAUAUAUGAGAUGCCAGGUUGUCAAUUUUCUAAACCUUUUCCUCUAGAUUAUUCUGGCCCUAGGCCUUUCAGCAACCCCACUAAUCAAUUAUUAGAUCCUGCCCCAAGGAGCAGUGGCUUGGGGGCUGGAUUUAGGGAGGAAAACCUGAUUAAACUGUUUUGCUUAGUACUGGUUACAGCUGUAGCUGGAGAAGAGUUUAUAAUCAUAAAGUACAUUUUUGUUAUUACCUUGUGGAUUUUAAUUAUCCAUCUUGUCUAAUCUUGUUCUCUGUCAUCCUAGAUAAUGAGGUGUUUGUGGGAGCAGAGCUCUGCACACACCAGGGGAUGUAAUAAAUGUUUGCACUUGGCCCAGUAUAUUAUGAAUGUGGCACAGUAAAUAAAGUUUGUGUACAAAAUACUAGUUUAUUUCUAUGGGAGCCAUUAUGUUCAGGAUAUAUAAAAUGUAUCUAAUUAAACAAUUUUGAAUCUAUUUUGUGCUCUAGAAAUGUUCUUUUGGGGAAAGAUGGAAAGAAAUGUAUAAAUGGAGUUAAGAUUAAAGUAUUUGGGGUUUUUUUUCCCCAAAAGCUUCCCAGUUGUUUAGAAAUAAUACUAUCCAAAGUAGGAUUCGGUCCUGUAAGUCCUAACUGAAUUUCUUUUGUAAAACUGAUACGUUUAAACUGUACAUUGCAUAAUCAUUCUGUUAAACUAAACCUUUGUUUAAUACAUAAUUGUAAGAGCAUAUAUUUGUUAUUGAAUUGAAAGACUUUUUUUGUAGCUUUUGCUUUUAAAGAAGAUGGCAAAUUAUCUAAGAAAGACUUAGCUUUAUUACGUCCAAAAUGAGAUCUAAAGAAGGAGGUCUUUAAAAAUUGUUGUGAUGGACCAACAUGUCCAACAUCUUAAGCAAAUGAAGCUUCAUGAUUAAGGCAGCUUACAGAUAAGUGGAAAAGAACUUACCUGUCAUAUGCAUCCUUUUGUUUUCCAAAACAACAUCUGAUUUAGUUCAUUUUCUCCAGCCUUGCUCCUAACAUAGUGAAAGGCAUAGAUACACAUGUAUGUUCUUUUACACUGUGUCAUUGUUUGUAAAAUAUACAGUAUUUAUGUACAGUUUCAGAGACAUUCAAUAUUGAAAACCACUUCAGUUAGCCUCCUAGUGAAUACUAUUAAUUUUUCAUGGAUUACAUAUUACCAUAUGACCCCAUAAAUACAUUUUAUUAGUUACUUUGGUAUCUUCAAAUUGGUAAGAAAAAAACAUAAAACAAAAAUGUUCUUAUUUUCUGCAAUUUUUUUUUCUAGCCAUUCCUUCCUCCCAAAUAGAAGUGAGGGCAAUUGUAGAGAGAGGAAUAUUAAGUUUUCAUAAAGCAAAGUAUCAUCUUAUUUGUGUUCCACCUGUUUCUUCUAACACUUAAUUCAUAAAGUGAGCAAUUGAACUUCUUAAUACUGUUAGAGAAUAUGCUAGAACUAUUACUUCUUUUAUCUUAGACACCCACUUUCCCUUAAUUCUCAUCUAUUUAGUUUUUUAAUAAAAUUGUUGCUAGAAUUUUUUUGUCUUUUCAAGUUCUUUUUUUGUUAAUUUUAUUGAUAUUGCUGUACUUUUUUUUUUUUUUUUGAGACAGAGUCUUGAGUGCUCUGUCACCCAGGCUGGAGCGCAAUGGCACAAUCUCGGCUCACUGCAGCCUCCGCCUCCCAGGUUCAAGGGAUUCUUGUGCCUCAGCCUCCCGAGUAGCUGGGUUUACAGGCGUGUGCCACCCACCUAGCUAAUUUUUGUAUUUUAGUUAGAGACGGGGGUUUUGCCAUGUUGGCCAGGCUGGUCUCGAACUCCUGACCUCAAGUGUUUCACCCGCCUCAGCCCCCCAAAGUGCUGGGAUUACAGGUGUGAGCAACCGCGCCUGGACUCAAGUUCUUUUUAAAGCUUGAUUAAGGUAUAACCGACAUAUAAUACACUUCGCAUAUUUGAACAGUACUUGAUACAGUUUGAUGUAUGUAUAUACCCUUGACAUAAUCAAAAUAGUGAACAUAUCUAUCAUCCCCAAAAGUUUCCCCUGCCCCUUUGUAAUCCUUCCCCAUCCUCUAUCCUGAGGCAACCAUUGAUCUGCUUUUAUUAUUUUUAAAAGUUAGCGUAUUUUCUUAUAUGUAUUGCAUAUGGGAUUUUUCUAGAAGGCCACGUGCAUAUGCACCCUCCCCUUCCAUUACCCCAGUAUCCGCCAUCAAGUAGUAACAUGUUGUAACAGAAAGAAUCCCAUUAAGUCCUAGUUCUGGUAGCCCGGUACAAAUUUUAGAUUUUCCCCCAAAAAUGAAAAAAAAUUAUUUAAAAAAUUUAGAUUUGAAAUGCUUAGAAAACAAUCAUUUAUUUUUUUAUGUCAAAAUGUCCAAGUAAAUUAAUGGAUUAAUUUCCAUGCUUCUGGUGAUGUAACACCACUUGGUGGUGGCGCUGAGGAAACCCUGGGAAGUGUUUUUCUCUUCUGUGUAAUGAAAGACUCACUGACAAAGCCGUCGGUAUCCAGAAUGACUGCUCUUGAAAUGAUAUUUUGAUGAUGAUGAUCAGGGAAGUAGCCUAUGCUGAUUUAUUUAUCAUCCCCCCACCCCAACCCCACUUUUGUGUCACAAACAUUUGAAACACCCAGUGCUCAAGAAUGCUGCUUUUCCAAUUCUGCUAAUAUCCUCUCUCCCCAUCUGGAAACAAAGUUACUAAACCUAGUUUUGAAAAAGCAAUGGAAAUGAAAGUGUCCAGUGAACUUACUGGCAGUUGUGCAAGUUGAAAGCUUAUUCCUUACAUCCUGAGCCUAAAAGCCUUAUUCCUUAUAUCCGGAGCCUAAAAGUUUGCUCAAAAGUAGAAAACUUUCCAGACAAGAUCACAUACAAAAUGGUUAACAUGAAAUGCUAAUGAAGAAACAAGGCAAGAAUGAAUACAAGAGAAAUGGAAUCUGGGGAAAAAAGUAGGUUCUCUAACUGGGGCAGGGAUCUUGCUUCUUGGGGGCAUAUGGUUGGAUCCCAGGUGGGCCACGAAAAUCAUCUUGGAUAUUUGUUUACAGGCUGAUUCCUGAGUUUCCCUCCAAAGAUUCUGAGUCCACAGAUCUAGGGUGUGGACCGAGAAUCCUCAUUGUAACAAGCACCCUCUGCCCCCGGGACAUUUUAAGGUAGAUGGAGAACUAAGGUGAGAGUGUGCCAGCUAAAUACUCUUUCCUUUGUCCCUGUGCCUCAGUCUUUUUUGUUUGUUUUUUUUCAUGUGACACUCAGUAGGAAAGUCUAGUUCAAGAACCGGAAACUGAGCCGGGCAUGGUGGUGCGCACCUGUAGUCCCAGCUACUCAGGAGGCUGAGGCAGGAGGAUGGCUUGAGCCUGACGCCCAUGCCGCUGUGAGCUAUGAUUGCACCACUGCCCUGAGCCUGGACGACAGAGCAAGUUCCUGUCUUAAAAAAAAAAGUAAUAAAAAAGACAUUUAAAAAAAAAUUAGAGCUCAGUGACCUGUGACUCACUUUGCCACUUUGUCAUUUUCUUGACUUCUGUCCCAACGCCAGCCCUGUAAUAUGGAGAUAAAGAGUGGGGAGGACAGAACUCUGAAACCUAAAAGGCAAGAUUUUUGCUAAACCGGAGAACGUAAAAAUACAUUCCUAGAGGCAAUCUAACCAGCCAGAUAACCAGAAGUUUACUCUUCAAAGCCAAGAAUCAGUACCCCCACCUCACCUUCCAUUCUCUCUUAGGCUUUGUCUAUGUCUCUAAGGGGAGUUUUUCAGUUGACUGAUGAGGUCCUGACUGGUAGGGAAAGCCUGCAGGGAAAUCCUGUGGCAAAGCACACUCUUGAUCACCUACUUAACAAGAAGGUCUAGCAGGACAUUCUUGAUCCAGGUCAGCUUCUUCCCUGAAAAUAAUACAUAUUUUUAAUUUCUGUUUGAAAAAACUCCACUGUGAAAUUACUCUGCUUAUAUUAGAAGGUAUGAAGACAGUAGUUAUGUACUGUUCGUUUGCAUACGGUCAUUUUGAGAUAGAAAAAUUAAAUUUUUUUAGGAAAAGAAUUUCAAGCAACUUUCUACGAAAAUACAGCUUGUGGUUAAAUUUCCUAAUGAAAGAGGAAUUAUUCACUGAAAAAUUUGUCUAAUCUGUGCCACCUCAAAAUAAGAAUUGUGCCUCUUCAAUGAAUGUUGUAUAUGAGAAUGUUACAUUUGUAACAGCACAGGAAACUCAAUAAAUUAUAAAUGAAUUACA